GCGGCUGACGUGGAGCGUCCGGGUUAGCGGGUGCGGCGAGCUGCGGGAUUGGGGAGCAACGGGCCGGGCCGGGCCUUCGGGCCCGAGGCGGCGGCGGCGGUAUAAAGCCGGCGACUGGGAGCAUGUAAUGUCGGAAUGCGGAGGCCGCGGCGGCGGCAGCAGCAGCAGCGAGGACGCCGAGGACGAGGGAGGGGGCGGCGGCGGCCCCGCGGGCUCAGACUGCCUCAGCUCGAGCCCGACCCUGGCCACAGCGUCCUCGGCGGGCCGGCUCCGUCGCGGGCUGCGUGGCGCCUUCCUCAUGGCGCGCCAGCGGCCGGAGCUGCUCUGCGGGGCCGUGGCGCUCGGCUGCGCGCUGCUCCUCGCCCUCAAGUUCACCUGCAGUCGAGCAAAAGAUGUGAUAAUACCAGCAAAGCCACCUGUCAGCUUUUUCUCCUUGAGGUCUCCAGUCCUUGACCUCUUCCAGGGGCAGCUGGAUUAUGCAGAGUACGUUCGACGGGAUUCAGAGGUGGUACUGCUCUUCUUCUAUGCCCCUUGGUGUGGACAGUCCAUCGCUGCCAGGGCAGAAAUUGAGCAAGCAGCAAGUCGGCUUUCAGAUCAGGUGUUGUUUGUGGCAAUUAACUGUUGGUGGAACCAGGGGAAAUGCAGAAAACAGAAACACUUCUUUUAUUUUCCUGUAAUAUAUCUGUAUCAUCGGAGUUUUGGACCAAUCGAAUACAAAGGCCCCAUGAGUGCUGUUUACAUUGAGAAGUUUGUCCGCCGGGUGAUGAAACCACUUCUCUACAUCCCAUCUCAAUCAGAAUUACUAGAUUUUCUCUCAAACUACGAGCCUGGAGUACUCGGGUACUUUGAGUUCAGUGGCUCACCCCAGCCUCCUGGUUAUUUGACCUUCUUCACCUCAGCAUUACAUUCAUUAAAGAAAGUAGAGACGGGGUUUCACCGUUUUCGCCAGCAUCGUCUUGAUCCCCGACCUCGUGAUCCGCCCACCUCGGCCUCCCAAAGUGCUGGAGUUACAGGCGUGAGCCAACGAGCGCGGCCAGAUGAUUACCUAGGAACAGUACGAUUUGGGGUUAUCACAAAUAAACAUCUUGCGAAACUGGUAUCCUUAGUACACUCUGGAAGUGUGUAUUUACAUAGACAUUUCAACACAUCACUUGUCUUCCCCAGGGAGGUCCUGAACUACACAGCUGAGAACAUCUGUAAGUGGGCCUUAGAAAACCAGGAGACGCUCUUUCGGUGGCUGCGGCCACACGGAGGCAAGAGUCUCCUGCUGAAUAACGAGCUGAAGAAAGGACCAGCGCUGUUUCUGUUCAUACCUUUUAAUCCCCUGGCCGAAAGUCAUCCUUUAAUAGACGAGAUCACCGAAGUGGCCUUGGAGUACAACAACUGUCAUGGGGACCAGGUGGUGGAGCGUCUCCUUCAGCACCUGCGGCGGGUGGAUGCUCCAGUGCUGGAGUCCCUGGCCCUGGAAGUGCCGGCACAGCUGCCAGACCCGCCAACGAUCACAGCGUCCCCCUGCUGCAACACUGUGGUGCUGCCCCAGUGGCACUCCUUCUCCAGGACCCACAACGUCUGUGAACUCUGUGUCAACCAGACCUCCGGGGGCAUGAAGCCGAGCUCGGUCAGCGUGCCACAGUGCAGCUUUUUUGAAAUGGCAGCAGCUCUGGAUUCUUUCUACCUCAAGGAGCAGACCUUUUAUCAUGUGGCAUCAGACAGCAUAGAAUGCAGCAAUUUUUUAACUUCCUAUAGCCCCUUCAGCUACUACACUGCAUGUUGCAGGACCAUAAGCAGGGGUGUGUCAGGCUUCAUCGACUCUGAACAAGGUGUCUUUGAAGCCCCUACUGUUGCAUUUUCUUCCCUUGAGAAGAAAUGUGAGGUUGAUGCCCCAAGCUCCGUUCCUCACAUUGAGGAGAACAGGUAUCUCUUUCCAGAAGUGGACAUGACUAGCACAAACUUCACAGGCCUGAGCUGCAGAACCAACAAGACUCUCAACAUCUACCUUUUGGAUUCAAAUUUGUUUUGGUUAUAUGCAGAGAGACUGGGUGCUCCGAGCUCCACUCAGGUGAAAGAAUUUGCGGCAAUUGUUGACGUGAAAGAAGAAUCUCAUUACAUCUUGGAUCCAAAGCAAGCACUGAUGAAGCUCACCCUAGAGUCUUUUAUUCAAAACUUCAGCGUUCUCUAUAGUCCCUUGAAAAGGCAUCUCAUUGGAAGUGGCUCUGCCCAGUUCCCGUCUCAGCAUUUAAUCACUGAAGUGACAACUGAUACCUUUUGGGAAGUAGUCCUUCAAAAACAGGACGUUCUCCUGCUCUAUUACGCUCCGUGGUGCGGCUUCUGUCCAUCCCUCAAUCACAUCUUCAUCCAGCUAGCUCGGAACCUGCCCAUGGACACAUUCACUGUGGCAAGGAUUGACGUGUCUCAGAAUGACCUUCCUUGGGAAUUUAUGGUCGAUCGUCUUCCUACUGUCUUGUUUUUUCCCUGCAACAGAAAGGACCUAAGUGUGAAAUACCCCGAAGACGUCCCCAUCACCCUUCCAAACCUGUUGAGGUUCAUUUUGCAUCACUCAGACCCUGCUUCCAGCCCCCAGAAUGUGGCUAACUCUCCUACCAAGGAGUGUCUUCAGAGCGAGGCAGUCUUACAGCGGGGGCACAUCUCCCACUUGGAGAGAGAGAUCCAGAAACUGAGAGCAGAAAUAAGCAGCCUCCAGCGAGCACAAGUGCAGGUGGAGUCCCAGCUCUCCAGUGCCCGCAGAGAUGAGCACCGGCUGCGGCAGCAGCAGCGGGCCCUGGAAGAGCAGCACAGCCUGCUCCACGCACACAGUGAGCAGCUGCAGGCCCUCUAUGAGCAGAAGACACGUGAGCUGCAGGAGCUGGCCCGCAAGCUGCAGGAGCUGGCCGAUGCCUCAGAAAACCUCCUUACCGAGAACACGUGGCUCAAGAUCCUGGUGGCGACCAUGGAGAGGAAACUGGAGGGCAGGGAUGGAGCUGAAAGCCUGGCGGCCCAGAGAGAGGUCCACCCCAAGCAGCCUGAGCCCUCAGCCACCCCCCAGCUCCCUGGCAGCUCCCCUCCACCUGCCAAUGUCAGCGCCACACUGGUGUCUGAAAGGAAUAAGGAGAACAGGACAGACUAACUUUUUAAAUGAUAUGAAGAAAUCAGAGGUGAAAAUUGUACAUUGGGAAUAUAUUUAUGCAAAUUUUAUUGAAAUUUAUUGUAAAUAAAGAUUUUCUCAGUGGUCUAGAAAA